CUUUCCCCUCCCCCUCCCUCUCCAAGCCGGAGGGGUCCUGAGGUGACAGCGCCUGCAACUGAAAUUUCAGCAGCGGGAGAAGAUGGACAAGAGAAAGCUCGGGCGACGGCCAUCUUCAUCCGAAAUCAUCACAGAAGGAAAAAGGAAAAAGUCAUCUUCUGAUUUAUCGGAGAUAAGAAAGAUGUUAAAUGCAAAACCAGAGGAUGUCCAUGUUCAAUCACCACUGUCCAAAUUCAGAAGCUCAGAACGCUGGACUCUCCCUUUGCAGGUGUGGGAAAGAAGCCUAAGGAAUAAAGUCAUCUCUCUAGACCAUAAAAAUAAAAAACAUAUCCGAGGGUGUCCUGUUACUUCCAAGUCAUCACCAGAAAGGCAACUCAAAGUUAUGUUGACGAAUGUCCUAUGGACGGAUUUAGGACGAAAAUUCAGAAAGACCCUACCUAGAAACGAUGCUAAUUUAUGUGAUGCCAACAAGGUGCAAUCAGACUCAUUGCCUUCGACAUCUGUUGACAGCCUAGAGACAUGUCAAAAAUUAGAACCUCUUCGCCAAAGCCUUAAUUUAUCUGAAAGGAUACCCAGAGUUAUAUUGACGAAUGUCCUGGGAACGGAGUUAGGAAGAAAAUACAUAAGGACCCCACCUGUAACUGAGGGAAGUUUGAGUGAUACAGACAACUUGCAAUCAGAGCAACUUUCUUCAUCAUCUGAUGGCAGCCUAGAAUCUUAUCAAAAUCUAAACCCUCACAAGAGCUGUUAUUUAUCUGAAAGGGGCUCACAACGAAGUAAGACAGUAGAUGACAAUUCUGCAAAGCAGACUGCGCACAAUAAAGAAAAACGAAGAAAGGAUGAUGGCAUUUCUCUUUUAAUAUCUGAUACUCAGCCUGAAGACCUUAACAGUGGAAGUAGAGGUUGUGAUCAUCUCGAACAGGAAAGCAGAAACAAGGAUGUUAAAUAUUCUGAUUCAAAAGUGGAACUCACUCUGAUUUCCAGGAAGACAAAGAGAAGGCUUAGAAAUAAUUUACCUGAUUCUCAAUAUUGUACUUCUUUGGAUAAGUCAACAGAACAGACAAAAAAACAAGAAGAUGACUCAACAAUAUCCACUGAGUUUGAAAAGCCAAGUGAAAACUAUCAUCAGGAUCCAAAACUGCCUGAAGAAAUUACAACUAAACCUACAAAAAGUGAUUUUACUAAACUAUCCUCACUUAACAGUCAGGAGUUGACUUUGAGUAAUGCCACCAAAAGUGCCUCUGCCGGUUCAACCACUGAAACCGUUGAGAACUCUAAUUCCAUUGAUAUUGUGGGGAUUUCUUCCCUGGUUGAGAAGGAUGAGAAUGAGUUGAAUACCAUAGAAAAGCCUAUUCUAAGAGGACAUAAUGAAGGGAACCAAUCACUGAUCUCAGCUGAACCAAUUGUUGUUUCCAGUGAUGAAGAAGGACCUGUUGAACAUAAAAGUUCAGAAAUUCUUAAGUUACAAUCUAAGCAAGACCGUGAGACAACUAAUGAAAAUGAGAGUACUUCUGAAUCAGCAUUGUUAGAACUACCAUUGAUUACAUGUGAAUCUGUACAGAUGUCAUCUGAAUUAUGCCCAUAUAAUCCUGUCAUGGAGAACAUUUCCAGUAUUAUGCCUAGUAAUGAGAUGGAUCUACAACUGGAUUUUAUAUUUACUUCUGUUUAUAUUGGUAAAAUAAAAGGAGCUUCUAAAGGUUGUGUUACAAUCACAAAAAAAUAUAUUAAGAUCCCAUUUCAAGUGUCCCUGAAUGAGAUUUCAUUGCUAGUGGAUACCACACAUUUAAAGCGGUUUGGGUUAUGGAAAAGUAAGGAUGAUAAUCACAGUAAAAGGAGUCAUGCUAUUCUUUUCUUCUGGGUCUCUUCAGAUUAUCUUCAAGAGAUUCAGACCCAAUUAGAACACUCUGUAUUAAGCCAGCAAUCAAAAUCUAGUGAAUUCAUUUUCCUUGAACUACACAAUCCUGUUUCACAAAGAGAAGAAUUGAAGCUGAAAGAUAUUAUGACGGAAAUAAGUAUAAUCAGUGGAGAAUUAGAGCUUUCUUACCCGUUGUCUUGGGUUCAGGCAUUUCCUUUGUUUCAGAACCUCUCUUCAAAAGAAAGUUCUUUUAUUCAUUAUUACUGUGUUUCAACUUGUUCUUUCCCUGCUGGUGUUGCUGUUGCUGAAGAAAUGAAGCUGAAAUCAGUAUCUCAGCCCUCAAACACAGAUGCGGCCAAGCCUACUUACACCUUCCUGCAGAAGCAAAGUAGCGGUUGCUACUCCCUUUCUAUUACAUCUAAUCCAGAUGAAGAAUGGCGAGAAGUCAGGCACACUGGACUUGUUCAGAAGUUGAUUGUAUAUCCUCCACCACCUACUAAGGGGGGAUUAGGAGUAACUAAUGAAGAUCUGGAGUGUUUAGAAGAAGGAGAGUUUCUUAAUGAUGUAAUCAUUGAUUUUUACCUUAAGUAUCUUAUAUUGGAGAAGGCAUCAGAUGAACUUGUUGAACGAAGUCACAUUUUUAGUAGCUUUUUCUAUAAAUGCUUGACAAGAAAGGAAAAUAAUUUAACAGAAGAUAAUCCAAAUCUUUCAAUGGCACAGAGAAGACAUAAAAGAGUAAGAACAUGGACUCGUCACAUAAACAUUUUUAAUAAAGAUUACAUCUUUGUACCUGUAAAUGAGUCGUCUCACUGGUAUCUCGCAGUCAUUUGUUUUCCAUGGUUAGAAGAAGCUGUGUAUGAAGAUUUUCCACAAACUGUAUCCCAGCAGUCCCAGGCUCAGCAGUCCCAAAAUGACAACAAAACAAUAGAUAAUGAUCUACGUACUACUUCGACACUGUCUUUGAGUGCAGAGGAUUCCCAAAGUACCGAGUCGAAUAUGUCAGUACCAAAGAAAAUGUGUAAAAGGCCAUGUAUUCUUAUACUAGACUCCUUGAAAGCUGCUUCUGUACAAAACACAGUUCAGAAUUUACGAGAGUAUUUAGAGGUAGAGUGGGAAGUUAAACUAAAAACUCAUCGUCAAUUCAGCAAAACAAACAUGGUGGAUCUAUGCCCUAAAGUUCCUAAACAGGACAAUAGCAGUGAUUGUGGAGUAUAUUUAUUGCAGUAUGUGGAAAGCUUCUUCAAGGAUCCUAUUGUUAACUUUGAACUUCCAAUUCAUUUGGAGAAGUGGUUUCCUCGUCAUGUAAUAAAGACCAAACGGGAAGAUAUUCGAGAGCUCAUCUUGAAACUUCAUUUACAGCAACAGAAGGGCAGCAGUAGCUAGUUAAUCUGUACAAACAUGACACAGAUGUUCUCUAAGAUUACUGGAAAGCCUCUUACCAGCAUUUGUGUUAGCCAGCUCACAGAGAAGAAAAUAACUUGCAGUAGUUUUAUAAUAAGUCAUUGGAACAUUAUUUAAAAUAUGUAGGACACAUUAUUAGAAUUGUUGGGAUCUCAUAGAUGGAAUGGGAAUGGGGGUGAUAUAGAUAAACUUACUAGAUAUAAAUUAAAAUUUUAUAAAUAUUUCAUAUUUUUCUGAGUAAAUAUGAUUGGAUUAUGCAACAGCAUAUGUAAUAUGGGAAUGUUUUGUAGAUAAUAAAACUUACAUGAUCUGUACUUCCACGUGACUGGGUGCUGAGGGGAGUUAAAGCCUCCCUGGUGCCAGCCCCAGUGCUUGUCAAAUUUGCUGACAGGUCACAUCAUAUUGUAAUUCUAUUCUUUGCAGCUCAAGCAUGCAGUAUGAAUACUGUGUAUUUUUUAAAAAAAUAAUUUAGUAUCAAGGCUUCAGAAAAUGCCAUUUACGGCAUCCCUUCUGUAUGUAACAAAAAGACAUUCAUAAUGUUAGGAAGAUGAUAAAAAUUCGCUCUUUUAAAGUGCAGCUUAUUAUUCUCAAUUGCUAAAUACGAUUACUCUGCUUUUUUUUUUUCAUUUCUUUUGAUGUCAUAUGUGAGUAUCUUAUAAUUUAGUUCAUUUGUUCAGGGUAAAAUUUGAAACAAAAAAUUUUACCUGUGCAAAAUAGUUUUUUAAAAAUUAUACAUGUAGCUCAACUUGAGGUACUGCUAUAUAAAUAUUCACUCACAUUAUCACGGAAUUUAUGUAUAGUUUCUCUAAUAUAGAAGAUAAAAUUGGUGUCCUCAUAACUUUAACAAAGAAAACCCUCAGUCCUAUUUAUUAAUGGGUAGAAUUAAAUAUAUAAUUUUAUAGCUCAGUUUACCCAGUAUUCAUCUGCAAAGCCAGAUUGCUCUCAUUGCUUUUAUAUUUUUAAAUUGUAGCUUUUAGAGACCUAUGAUCCUCAUGGAACUUAAUUUUUUAUUAAAUAUUCAGGUAACAGUUCUGAAUUCAUGUGAUAAUGGUGGCAUUAUAUAUGAUUAAACACUUCAGAACUUUCUAAUGUUAUCAGGAGUAUUUUGAGGGAGAUAUGAUUAUAUUGUAUUUUCUCAGAUAAGAAAAAUGUUUUUUAACAAUAUUAUUUUAAUCUGUUUUAAGCAUCUCUUAGAUUUACAUUAUAACUACAUAAAGCAGUGAAGCAAAGGCAAAUUAAGAUAAAGCUAGAAAGUCUGAACAUUUUAUUUCAAAAUCAUACGAAUCGGGGUCAGUUAAGCCUCAGUAUUCUUAGCUUUUGUUGAUUUUGGCACUAUCUUUAUAUUAUUAAAUAUAUUUGUUGUUUGGAUAUUUCAUAUAAAGAUGGCUAUAAUUACAUAUUUCAUUCCCAAUUUGUGUGUGUUGGGGGGUACUUUUAAAGGUGACUAUUGUUUUGUACAUCUAAUUUUGGGAAAGCAAGUCUAUAAGACAUCUUGUGAUUUCUUAAUGUUUUUGUUUGUAUGUUUUUCAAAGAUAUCACUGUCCUUUAUCAUGUUUUGAAGAUUGUUUAAAAUUCAUUUUCCUAAAUUAAUGUGCAAGUAAUGUUUUGAGGAUAUCAGUGUUUUAUAUUAAACAUAUUUCCAAUUCAUUAAAUUGAGGUGUAAUUUUUUUCCUUAAGAAACAUGAGCUACUGUUAGAAAUAAAUUUCCAGUUGUAUGCUG